AGAAGUUCUCAACACAUCCUUUAAGGUUCCAAACAUCUACUAGAAAAGGAGUGCAGAUUUAAACUGAGUGAGGUGUGGAGUGGGGGAAGCUGACUGUGUCUGGAACAAAGAACUUUGAGGAACUUGCCCAGAGCCCUGCACUCAUCAGACCUGCAGCAGACAUUGCAGGCCUGAAGAAAGCACCUUUUCUGCUGCCAUGACAACCAUGCAAGGAAUGGAACAGACCACUCCAGGGGCUGGCCCUGAUGUGCCCCAGCUGGGAAACAUAGAUGUCAUACAUUCAUAUCUGUGUAAAGGAUUGCAAGAGAAGUUCUUCAAGAGGAAACCCAAAGUCCUUGGGGUUUUGUGUGGACAUAAGUUUUCAACUCAUUCGGUAUCCUUAUCAGUUGCAGCAGGAAUUAGAACAACAAAAGGUCUGGUUGGAGGUAGUCUAGGAAAGAAUAUCACCAGUUCAGUCUUGGCUAUAUCAGGGAUCUUAAUCAAUGCAAUAAGCUUGACGUUUUAUUCAUUCCGUUACCAUUACUGUAACCACGAUCAGUUGUCAAGUAAUUGUUACAUGACUAUGUCCAUUUUAAUGGGUACGGAUGGCAUGGUGCUCCUCUUAAGUGUGCUGGAAUUCUGCAUUGCUGUGGCCCUCUCUGCCUUUGGAUGUAAAGUGCUUUGUUGUAGCCCCAGUGAGAGCAAAAAUAAAAUUAGAAGCAAUACUUUCAUGUGCUACCUCCUUUCUAUUCAGAUGCAAUAUGAUGGAAAGAGACUAAAUGUUGAUGUCGACAGUACUGUAUGGUGCUCCGGAGAUGGACAGUAUCUGGAAAAAGUCUAUUAUGACAUUCUAUCUUCUUGGUUGAGGAUUGAAAGUAUUUAUCGAGUGCUCAAUGGUGCCCAGGCUGGAGUGCAGUGGCGUGAUCUCGGCUCCCUACAACCUCCACCUCCCAGCCGCCUGCCUUGGCCUCCCAAAGUGCCGAGAGUGCAGCCUCUGCCCGGCCGCCACCCCGUCUGGGAAGUGAGGAGCGUCUCUGCCUGGCCGCCUAUCGUCUGGGACGUGAGGAGCCCCUCUGCCUGGCUGCCCAGUCUGGAAAGUGAGGAGCGUCUCUGCCCGGCUGCCAUCCCAUCUAGGAAGUGGGGAGCGCCUCUUCCCGGCCACCAUCCCAUCUGGGAGGUGAGGAGUGUCUCCGCCCGGCCGCCCAUCUUCUGAGAUGUGGGGAGCGCCUUUGCCCCACCGCCCUGUCUGGGAUGUGAGGAGCACCUCUGCCCGGCCGCGACCCCGUCUGGGAGGUGAGGAGCGUCUCUGCCCAGCCGCCCCAUCUGAGAAGGGAGGAGACCCUCCGCCUGGCAACCGCCCCGUCUGAGAAGUGAGGAGCCCCUCCGCCCGGCAGCCACCCCGUCUGGGAAGUGAGGAGCGUCUCCGCCAGGCAGCCACCCCGUCCGGGAGGGAGGUGGGGGUCAGCCCCCGCCAGGCCAGCUGCCCCAUCCGGGAGGGAGGUGGGGGGGGUCAGCCCCCCGCCCGGCCAGCCGCCCCGUCCGGGAGGUGAGGGGCGCCUCUGCCCAGCCGCCCCUACUGGGAAGUGAGGAGCCCCUCUACCCGGCCAGCCGCUCCGUCCGGGAGGGAGGUGGGGGGGUCAGACCCCGCCCGGCCAGCCGCCCCGUCCGGGAGGGAGGUGGGGGGUUCAGCCCCCCACCCGGCCAGCCACCACGUCUGGGAGGGAGGUGGGGGGGUCAGCCCUCUGCCCGGCCAGCCGCCCCGUCCGGGAGGGAGGUGGGGGGUUCAGCCCCCCACCCGGCCAGCCGCCCCGUCCGGGAGGGAGGUGGAGGGGUCAGCCCCCCGCCCGGCCAGCCGCCCCGUCCGGGAGGUGAGGGGUGCCUCUGCCCAGCCGCCCCUACUGGGAAGUGAGGAGCCCCUCUGCCCGGCCACCACCCCAUCUGGGAAGUGUACCCAAUAGCUCAUUGAGAACGGGCCAUGAGGACAAUGGCGGUUUUGUGGAAUAGAAAGGGGGGAAAGGUGGGGAAAAGAUUGAGAAAUCGGAUGGUUGCCUUGUCUGUGUGGAAAGAAGUAGACAUGGGAGACUUUUCAUUUUGUUCUGUACUAAGAAAAAUUCUUCUGCCUUGGGAUCCUGUUGAUCUGUGACCUUACCCCCAACCCUGUGCUCUCUGAAACAUGUGCUGUGUCCACUCAGGGUUAAAUGGAUUAAGGGCGGUGCAAGGUGUGCUUUGUUAAACAGAUGCUUGAAGGCAGCAUGCUCGUUAAGAGUCAUCACCACUCCCUAAUCUCAAGUACCCAGGGACACAAACACCUCGGAAGGCCGCAGGGUCCUCUGCCUAGGAAAACCAGAGACCUUUGUUCACUUGUUUAUCUGCUGACCUUCCCUCCACUAUUGUCCUAUGACCCUGCCAAAUCCCCCUCUGUGAGAAACACCCAAGAAUGGUCAAUAAAAAAUUAAAUAAAUAAAUAAAUAAAUAAAUAAAAAGUA